GACAGAGUCUCAGCCUCGCCGCUGCUGCCGCCGCCGCCGCCCAGAGACUGCUGAGCCCGUCCGUCCGCCGCCACCACCCACUCCGGACACAGGUGAGGAACCCGGCCGCCGCCGCGCCUCGCUUCCUGUCCCAGGCCAGCCUUCCGAACGCGUGGGAGCCGUCCUCGCUCCGUCCCCUCAUCCCCACUCGCCCCGCGGUGGCGGCGCCGGGCUGAGGCGGAGUCUCCUCAGCGGACACGGGCGGCGGCUCCUCUUCCGCUGGGCUCGGGAGGGCGGCUAGCGGCCGCCUCCGGCUCCUUGCUUCCGCAUCGACGCCCCGGCGCCGAUCGGUGCUCGCUCCCCCGUCCUGCCCCCGGGGGUGGGUAGGGCGCCCACACGCGAGAUCCCUGGGGAUCUCCCUGUCGCCGGCUCCCGAAGGUGGACGAGGCAUGGCCGGGGCGCCGCCGGCCGCGAUCCAUCCCCACCCUUGUCUCUGCGGGCUUCCACCCCCUCCCUCGCCGCCCUUCUCGCUUCCGCCCGAGAUAAUGACUCGGCGGCGGCGGCGGCGGGCAUCGCAGUGGCGCAGAACAUCCAGUCAUGGAUAAAAAUGAGCUGGUUCAGAAGGCCAAACUGGCCGAGCAGGCUGAGCGAUAUGAUGACAUGGCAGCCUGCAUGAAGUCUGUAACUGAGCAAGGAGCUGAAUUAUCCAAUGAGGAGAGGAAUCUUCUCUCAGUUGCUUAUAAAAAUGUUGUAGGAGCCCGUAGGUCAUCUUGGAGGGUCGUCUCAAGUAUUGAACAAAAGACGGAAGGUGCUGAGAAAAAACAGCAGAUGGCUCGAGAAUACAGAGAGAAAAUUGAGACGGAGCUAAGAGAUAUCUGCAAUGAUGUACUGUCUCUUUUGGAAAAGUUCUUGAUCCCCAAUGCUUCACAAGCAGAGAGCAAAGUCUUCUAUUUGAAAAUGAAAGGAGAUUACUACCGUUACUUGGCUGAGGUUGCCGCUGGUGAUGACAAGAAAGGGAUUGUCGAUCAGUCACAACAAGCAUACCAAGAAGCUUUUGAAAUCAGCAAAAAGGAAAUGCAACCAACACAUCCUAUCAGACUGGGUCUGGCCCUUAACUUCUCUGUGUUCUAUUAUGAGAUUCUGAACUCCCCAGAGAAAGCCUGCUCUCUUGCAAAGACAGCUUUUGAUGAAGCCAUUGCUGAACUUGAUACAUUAAGUGAAGAGUCAUACAAAGACAGCACGCUAAUAAUGCAAUUACUGAGAGACAACUUGACAUUGUGGACAUCGGAUACCCAAGGAGACGAAGCUGAAGCAGGAGAAGGAGGGGAAAAUUAACCGGCCUUCCAACUUUUGUCUGCCUCAUUCUAAAAUUUACACAGUAGACCAUUUGUCAUCCAUGCUGUCCCACAAAUAGUUUUUUGUUUACGAUUUAUGACAGGUUUAUGUUACUUCUAUUUGAAUUUCUAUAUUUCCCAUGUGGUUUUUAUGUUUAAUAUUAGGGGAGUAGAGCCAGUUAACAUUUAGGGAGUUAUCUGUUUUCAUCUUGAGGUGGCCAAUAUGGGGAUGUGGAAUUUUUAUACAAGUUAUAAGUGUUUGGCAUAGUACUUUUGGUACAUUGUGGCUUCAAAAGGGCCAGUGUAAAACUGCUUCCAUGUCUAAGCAAAGAAAACUGCCUACAUACUGGUUUGUCCUGGCGGGGAAUAAAAGGGAUCAUUGGUUCCAGUCACAGGUGUAGUAAUUGUGGGUACUUUAAGGUUUGGAGCACUUACAAGGCUGUGGUAGAAUCAUACCCCAUGGAUACCACAUAUUAAACCAUGUAUAUCUGUGGAAUACUCAAUGUGUACACCUUUGACUACAGCUGCAGAAGUGUUCCUUUAGACAAAGUUGUGACCCAUUUUACUCUGGAUAAGGGCAGAAACGGUUCACAUUCCAUUAUUUGUAAAGUUACCUGCUGUUAGCUUUCAUUAUUUUUGCUACACUCAUUUUAUUUGUAUUUAAAUGUUUUAGGCAACCUAAGAACAAAUGUAAAAGUAAAGAUGCAGGAAAAAUGAAUUGCUUGGUAUUCAUUACUUCAUGUAUAUCAAGCACAGCAGUAAAACAAAAACCCAUGUAUUUAACUUUUUUUUAGGAUUUUUGCUUUUGUGAUUUUUUUUUUUUUGAUACUUGCCUAACAUGCAUGUGCUGUAAAAAUAGUUAACAGGGAAAUAACUUGAGAUGAUGGCUAGCUUUGUUUAAUGUCUUAUGAAAUUUUCAUGAACAAUCCAAGCAUAAUUGUUAAGAACACGUGUAUUAAAUUCAUGUAAGUGGAAUAAAAGUUUUAUGAAUGGACUUUUCAACUACUUUCUCUACAGCUUUUCAUGUAAAUUAGUCUUGGUUCUGAAACUUCUCUAAAGGAAAUUGUACAUUUUUUGAAAUUUAUUCCUUAUUCCCUCUUGGCAGCUAAUGGGCUCUUACCAAGUUUAAACACAAAAUUUAUCAUAACAAAAAUACUACUAAUAUAACUACUGUUUCCAUGUCCCAUGAUCCCCUCUCUUCCUCCCCACCCUGAAAAAAAUGAGUUCCUAUUUUUUCUGGGAGAGGGGGGGAUUGAUUAGAAAAAAAUGUAGUGUGUUCCAUUUAAAAUUUUGGCAUAUGGCAUUUUCUAACUUAGGAAGCCACAAUGUUCUUGGCCCAUCAUGACAUUGGGUAGCAUUAACUGUAAGUUUUGUGCUUCCAAAUCACUUUUUGGUUUUUAAGAAUUUCUUGAUACUCUUAUAGCCUGCCUUCAAUUUUGAUCCUUUAUUCUUUCUAUUUGUCAGGUGCACAAGAUUACCUUCCUGUUUUAGCCUUCUGUCUUGUCACCAACCAUUCUUACUUGGUGGCCAUGUACUUGGAAAAAGGCCGCAUGAUCUUUCUGGCUCCACUCAGUGUCUAAGGCACCCUGCUUCCUUUGCUUGCAUCCCACAGACUAUUUCCCUCAUCCUAUUUACUGCAGCAAAUCUCUCCUUAGUUGAUGAGACUGUGUUUAUCUCCCUUUAAAACCCUACCUAUCCUGAAUGGUCUGUCAUUGUCUGCCUUUAAAAUCCUUCCUCUUUCUUCCUCCUCUAUUCUCUAAAUAAUGAUGGGGCUAAGUUAUACCCAAAGCUCACUUUACAAAAUAUUUCCUCAGUACUUUGCAGAAAACACCAAACAAAAAUGCCAUUUUAAAAAAGGUGUAUUUUUUCUUUUAGAAUGUAAGCUCCUCAAGAGCAGGGACAAUGUUUUCUGUAUGUUCUAUUGUGCCUAGUACACUGUAAAUGCUCAAUAAAUAUUGAUGAUGGGAGGCAGUGAGUCUUGAUGAUAAGGGUGAGAAACUGAAAUCCCAAACACUGUUUUGUUGCUUGUUUUAUUAUGACCUCAGAUUAAAUUGGGAAAUAUUGGCCCUUUUGAAUAAUUGUCCCAAAUAUUACAUUCAAAUAAAAGUGCAAUGGAGACCUUGGGGUCUUUAUUUCCAGGAGAAAAGAUACCUUCUGCAUCUAGGGCAACAAUCCUUUUCCCUCGCAGCUCUUUCUUUUACCUCACUUACUGAUUUCUCCUGACCCCCAAGCCAAGGAGGUAAAAUAAUUAUAUAUAUAUAUAUAUAUAUAUAUAUAUAUAUAUAAAGUAAUUAUAUUUUAUAGCUAGACUGAAGAGGUGGGAAUUUUUUUGUUGUUUUUUUUUUUUUUGGAGACAAGAGUCUUGCUCUGUCACCCAGGCUUGAGUGCAGUGGUGCGAUCUCGGCUGAGUGCAACCUCCGCCUGCUGGGUUCAAGCGAUUCUCCUGCCUCAGCCUCCCAAGUAGCUGGGAUUACAGGUGCCCGCCACCACACCUGGCUAAUUUUUGUGUUUUUAGUAGAGACAGGGUUUCACCAUGUUGUCCAGGCUGGUCUUGAAUUCCCGACCUCAGGCAAUCCGCCCAUCUCAACCUCCCAAAGUGCUGGGAUUACAGGCAUAAGCCACCGCGCCCAGUAGAGAUGUGAUAUUAUUCAAGUAAAUAAAACCUGAAACUUGGCACAUUUGCCUAUUUAAUGUGCAUCAGUCAUCUGAACUAGGUUGAUCCUGGAAUAAUGAAAACACUUCACUAGUAUUAACUAAUGUUUUCUACAUAGUAGUUCCCAAUAGAUUAAGGAAAAUUUCCAACCUGAGAUUCUUUGUUUUGGAAUUUGAAUAAUGUGUUUGUAACUAUUCCUUGAUUGUCCCAAAUCCAGGCUUUACGUCUGCUUUUGUCAAUGUAACAUCCUAGUGCCAGGAAAUUGGAAAAUCCAAUGACUUUUUGUGUGUAAAGUACUGGAAUUUUUUUGUUCGUUUGUUUUUAAGACGGAGUGUCAACUCUCGCCCAGGCUGGGGUGCAGUGGCCUGAUCUCGGCUCACUGCAACCUUCUCCUCCCAGGCUGAAGUGAUUCUCCUGCCUCAGCCUCGCAAGUAGCUGGGACUGCAGGCAUGUGCCACCACUCCUGGCUAAUUAUUUGUAUUUUUAGUAGAGAGAGGGUUUCACCGUGUUAGCCAUGAUGGUCUCAUUCUCCUGACCUUGUGAUCCGCCCACCUCGGCCUCCCAAAGUGCUGGGAUUACAGGCGUGAGCCACUGUGCCCACCCUGGUAUGUUUUUUUUAAAUUGGCCACUUAAGAGUUGUCCUUCAGAAAGUGGAGCAGCAGUGUGAUUAGUAAAAACGAUGGGCUUUCCUGCAGCUCUGGCUUAUGGUCUUUGUUUUUCCAGUUAACAGCUGUUACUUCAUGCUGUUAUAGGGGGUGGGGGGAGAAAGAGAAAGAAUAUGUCUAGUGGCUUAAUUUUGGGGCUCAAUUUGUUUAUUAUGUUUUUCCUGCAAAAGAGUCACCAGUCUUGUCAUGGCUCAAUGCAUAUUUUAAAAUGAGUCAAAGCCAAUUUGGAAGCUGCUAUCUUAGGUUAUUUGUAGUCAGGCUUCAAAUGGAGAGUGAAACUUUGACUUUGAAAACUGGUGCUCUAUGCUCAAUGAUGGUCUUACACAUUCCUCUAGGGAAAGGUCAAGAAAUAAAUUUGGCUUGAUUGUAUUCUCUCAUUUACCAUAUAGGAAAUACUAUGGUAGAACUGAAAAUAUGUACAAUAGUAAAGUGGUGGCUGAGACUGGGCACUUGGAAAAUAGACUUGGAUUCUUUUCUAAGUGUGAAACUAAUUAAAUACUUUUAUGUGACUGGUAGUAGUCACAGUCUCCUUGAUUGAUUCUAGUUCCUUUUCAAAGUGGAGAGACCUGAAUAUAGAUUGUAACAGGAUGUCCAACCUUGCCAGACAAGCAGGCAUAUAUGUCUCUGGGAUGCAGAAGCAGUUACAAGUUAAUAUAUUUAAGCAUAAUGUUAGCCAAUCCUAGGUGAUACCAGAGAUGUGAAUAUUUGAUCAUAUUUGAGUUCAUUCCUUGAAAGUCCAAACCUAACUGGUCUUAAUUGAUUACUUCUUAGUAUUCCGAAUUUUAGAAUUUAAAACCCUAUGAAUUUUCAGUUUGUGCUUACAUUUUCUAACAUUGGAUGUUUGCUUUGGCCA